ACUUCCGAAGAGAGAACCGCCAUGAAGAGAGAAGGGGGUGCCGCCCACCUCUGCUCCGACAGCCUCCCGGAGUCCCAGCAGCAAGACGGCAACCACGCACCCAACUUCUCCAGCCACGGCUCAUGCCGCCGUCGCCAGCGGCGCCGACAUGACAAGGCGCUGCAUGCCCGCUAGGCCAGGUUUCCCCUCAUCCCCAGCCCCGGGGUCGUCGCCCCCGCGCUGCCAUCUGAGACCCGGUAGUACCGCCCAUGCUGCAGCGGGAAAGAGAACAGAGAGUCCUGGGGACAGGUACCGUGCAGAGGGCUUGAGAAGGGGCCGGGUCGCGGGGGCAAGGGUAUGAGGGGAGGGCUGCAGACCGCCGCUCUUCCAGUUCCCGCCAUCCUCCGCGAGCUCAGGCGUUGGCAUUUCGGGGCCUGGCAAAUCCCCGCCCCGCCUCCGCGCAGGGGCUACUGGGAGUUGGAGUUUGCUUCUCUGUAGUUGGGCAGCUGCUCUUGGUCUAGUGACCACCAGCCUGGACAGCUACGGAGAACCCGCCUUAGGUAGAAAGAAAGUGAUUUUUUUCCUUUGCAAGAGUUUGACCCGGGACCCUAACUGCUUAAUGCAUAUUUAGAUCGUUUUCUGUACGUUGUCAGUUCUACUGAUCCUAGUGGUUUAGUAAUAUAAACCUUUUCUAUGUUGUGGGUGAAAUUAUGUAACCUGUGAUGAGGGAAUCCCUUCCACGAAUUACUUUGUAGUCCAGCGUGCACGCUAGUUCAUACUUAAAAGAACUUGCAGAUUUGGAAUGUGACGUGUUUUCUCUUUCAGUAACUUCACGCCUCUCCAAGAGGCUAAUUUUUUUGUAAAGAUUUUGUGGGAGCUAUGUAAUGAGAUGGGGAGUUUCAUCUAAUGACAUCCUCUGACAAUAAAACAUGUUUAAAUUCCCUACGAACUUGGUACUGUCUUUUAUUUUAAGUUAAAUUGUAUUAAGUUUUAACAAUAUUCAUGUUACUAAUACUGUGGUACAGGCCCACAAUCCCUUAUCUUAACUCUGAAAGCCAGAAAGCUAUGAAAACCAAAACGUUUUCAGUAAGUUUGGCACCACAUCUUACUGGGCAGCCAGAUCUGACUAAAACUAAUGUAAGGCUGUUUGUGGUCUUUAUCCCAUUAAGUGUGAAUAUUCAUGUUUUGCUGGAGAAAUGUCAGUGGAUUUGAUUACAGGUUGCAGCACCAGACCCCACUGGGGACUUUCCAUAAUACAUCCAAGUUAUCCCCUUCCUAAAAUCUGAUAAAUUCAGAAUUCUAAAACACAUUUGGCCCCAGAAGGUUCAGAUAAGGGUUUGUGAAACUGUUAUAAUUGUGUGUGUGUGUGUGUUUUUUUUUAAGCCAGUUGUUAAAUAAGCAGUGGACAUUUUGUGUGCAUAUGAACUUAGAGAACCUACCUCUUGAAAGUUACAUUCAUGGUUAUUUUACAGGUUUCUUGUAUGUUUUACCCAAAAUCAUUUUUUCUCUUUCUGGUGUAUUAAUCAAAAAGGAGUCUGAGGUCCAAUAUUUUAGGGAAGAGAUACAGUGUUACAUUUAGUAAAAUGCAUUUAGAAUUAUCUUGUGUGCAACAAAUGAGCUGCUUCUGGGUCCCUUCCCAUCUCUCCUCAAUCAAUAACAAGAUCAAUAACAAGGUAUCAUCCUUCUUCCCUUUGCAGAACCUCCAACAUUUACUCUGGUGGAGUUAAUUUGCCUAGUAUAAUUUAUGUAAACAAAUGCAUAUAUUCUUCCAUAGCCCGUCACUCAUAUUCAUCUCAUAAGCACUUAGCUUUUAUACCAGCAUCUCAAACAAGCGUGAUGGACUUGGUAAACCAGUAAAGAUGUGCAUUGCUCUUCUAAUGUGACCAGUAAAGUGUACAAGAAGCUUAACCUUCAAGAAACUUGGAUUGUUGGAAUUUUCACUGAGCAUUCCAACCUCAUAGUGGAUGAAUGUUUAGGGAAAUCAAUAGUCUAUAGCUUAUUCUCUUUCAGUAAAAUGAUACAUUUUAGCAAAAUUUACCAGAAAGUUAAUUUUUUGUUCAGCAUAUCAUAACAUCCCCUUUUUUGCAGCUGACAACUCUACAGUGAACAAAUCAGAAUACGAAUUCUGGAAGCAGUCAAUUAUAGAUUUCUUCAAACCAGCUUCAAAACAAGACAGACACAUGUUGGAUUCACCACAAAAAUCAAACAUCAAAUAUGGAGGAAGUAGAUUGUCUAUCACUGGGACAGAGCAGUUUGAAAGGAAACUAUCCUCACCAAAAGAAUCUAAACCCAAAAGGGUGCCACCAGAAAAGAGCCCUAUUAUAGAAGCUUUCAUGAAAGGUGUUAAAGAGCACCAUGAAGAUCAUGGUAUACAUGAGUCACGUCGGCCUUGUCUGUCACUAGCCUCCAAAUAUUUAGCCAAAGGAACAAAUAUCUAUGUUCCUUCUUCAUAUCACUUGCCAAAGGAGAUGAAGUCACUAAAGAAAAAACAUCGAUCCCCAGAGAGAAGGAAGUCACUAUUCAUUCAUGAAAAUAAUGAGAAGAAUGAUAGAGAUCGAGGCAAAACCAAUGCAGACUCCAAAAAGCAGACCACAGUGGCAGAAGCUGACAUCUUCAAUAACAGCUCCAGAAGCCUUAGCAGCAGGAGCAGCCUGUCCAGGCACCACCCGGAAGAAAGCCCACUGGGAGCUAAAUUCCAGUUGUCACUAGCUUCUUACUGCAGAGAACGAGAACUAAAGAGGUUGAGAAAGGAGCAAAUGGAGCAGAGAAUCAACUCCGAGAAUUCUUUCUCAGAAGCAAGCAGUCUUUCCUUAAAAUCUAGUAUAGAAAGAAAAUAUAAACCAAGGCAGGAACAAAGGAAACAGAAUGACAUCAUACCUGGAAAAAAUAAUCUGUCAAAUGUGGAAAAUGGACAUCUCUCAAGAAAAAGAUCCUCUUCUGAUUCAUGGGAACCUACUUCAGCAGGCUCUAAGCAGAAUAAAUUCCCUGAAAAAAGAAAAAGGAACUCUGUGGACUCAGAUCUGAAAAGCACAAGAGAAUCUAUGAUACCAAAAGCAAGAGAGUCCUUCCUUGAGAAGCGUCCUGAUGGACCACAUCAGAAAGAAAAAUUUAUAAAACAUAUUGCACUGAAGACACCUGGUGAUGUGUUGCGCUUAGAAGAUAUAUCCAAGGAACCGAGUGAUGAAACUGAUGGCUCUUCUGCAGGCUUGGCACCUUCAAAUUCUGGCAAUUCUGGCCACCAUUCUACCAGGAAUAGUGACCAAAUCCAAGUGGCAGGUACCAAGGAGACUAAGAUGCAGAAACCCCACUUACCUUUAUCUCAGGAAAAGUCUGCAAUUAAAAAAGCUAGCAACCUUCAGAAAAAUAAAACCGCUAGCUCCACGACAAAGGAGAAGGAGACAAAACUACCUUUACUUUCCCGUGUUCCAAGUGCUGGUUCCUCUCUAGUACCAUUAAAUGCUAAAAAUUGUGCUCUUCCAGUUUCUAAAAAAGAUAAAGAGCGUUCCUCAUCUAAAGAAUGUUCUGGGCAUUCUACAGAAUCCACCAAACACAAGGAACACAAAGCAAAGACUAAUAAGGCCGAUUCUAAUGUAUCUUCAGGGAAAAUUUCUGGGGGACCUUUGCGCUCAGAAUAUGGCACUCCUACAAAGUCUCCCCCUGCUGCUUUGGAAGUUGUGCCAUGUAUCCCAAGCCCUGCAGCACCUUCAGAUAAAGCCCCUUCAGAAGGAGAGAGUUCAGGAAAUUCCAAUGCAGGUAGCAGUGCACUGAAAAGAAAACUAAGGGGUGAUUUUGAUAGUGAUGAAGAAAGUUUAGGUUACAACCUAGACAGUGAUGAGGAAGAGGAAACAUUAAAGUCACUGGAAGAAAUAAUGGCUUUGAACUUCAAUCAGACUCCUGCAGCUACAGGAAAGCCUCCUGCUCUUUCCAAGGGGCUUAGAUCUCAGUCAUCAGACUAUACAGGACAUGUUCAUCCUGGAACUUACACAAAUACCUUAGAACGUCUAGUGAAGGAAAUGGAAGACACACAAAGGCUAGAUGAACUGCAGAAGCAACUACAAGAAGACAUAAGGCAAGGCCGAGGCAUUAAAUCCCCAAUCAGAAUUGGAGAAGAAGACAGUACAGAUGAUGAGGAUGGCCUCUUAGAAGAGCACAAGGAAUUUCUAAAGAAAUUUUCAGUUACAAUUGAUGCUAUUCCUGAUCAUCAUCCAGGUGAAGAAAUAUUUAAUUUCCUCAAUUCUGGAAAAAUUUUCAAUCAGUAUACCUUGGAUUUAAGAGACUCUGGUUUUAUUGGACAAAGUGCUGUAGAAAAACUUAUUCUUAAAUCGGGAAAAACAGAUCAGAUUUUUUUGACAACACAAGGUUUCCUUACGUCUGCUUAUCACUAUGUCCAGUGUCCUGUCCCUGUGUUAAAGUGGCUGUUUCGGAUGAUGUCAGUUCAUACAGACUGUAUUGUGUCAGUGCAGAUUUUAAGUACAUUGAUGGAAAUAACAAUUAGAAAUGAUACCUUCAGUGACUCACCAGUUUGGCCAUGGAUCCCAUCAUUGUCUGAUGUAGCAGCUGUGUUUUUCAAUAUGGGGAUUGAUUUUAGAUCUUUGUUUCCCCUGGAGAAUCUUCAGCCAGACUUUAAUGAAGACUAUCUAGUUUCUGAAACACAGACAACAUCAAGGGGGAAAGAAAGUGAAGAUUCAUCUUAUAAGCCAAUUUUUUCAACACUUCCUGAAACCAACAUUUUAAAUGUGGUUAAGUUUCUAGGCUUGUGUACAUCUAUACAUCCAGAAGGUUACCAGGAUCGUGAAAUAAUGUUGCUGAUUUUAAUGUUAUUUAAAAUGAGUUUGGAAAAACAGCUGAAACAGAUUCCUUUAGUAGACUUUCAAAGCCUCCUGAUAAACCUGAUGAAAAACAUCAGAGAUUGGAACACAAAGGUGCCUGAACUCUGUCUGGGCAUAAAUGAACUCUCCAGUCAUCCCCACAACCUCCUGUGGUUGGUACAGCUGGUCCCUAAUUGGACAUCACGUGGAAGGCAACUGAGACAGUGCCUCAGUCUAGUGAUUAUUUCAAAGCUUUUGGAUGAGAAACACGAAGAUGUUCCUAAUGCCAGUAAUCUGCAGGUAUCAGUCCUACAUCGCUAUCUUGUGCAGAUGAAGCCUUCUGAUUUGUUAAAGAAAAUGGUCUUGAAGAAAAAGGCUGAACAACCAGAUGGCAUUAUUGAUGACAGUCUUCAUUUAGAACUUGAAAAGCAGGCAUAUUACCUGACCUACAUUCUUCUUCAUUUAGUCGGUGAAGUUAGUUGUUCUCAUUCUUUUUCUUCUGGACAACGGAAACACUUUGUGCUACUCUGUGGGGCUUUGGAAAAGCAUGUUAAAUGUGAUAUUAGGGAAGAUGCAAGACUUUUUUACAGAACUAAGGUGAAAGACUUGGUCGCCAGGAUACAUGGAAAAUGGCAGGAAAUAAUCCAGAACUGUCGGCCUACUCAGGGGCAGCUUCAUGACUUCUGGGUACCAGAUUCUUAAUAGGAGUUGCAGCAGCAAAAAUAUGAACCAAGAGAAAUUCAAUAAGAGCCUUUCAUAGAGGAGUAGAAAGGAUUAUUACAGAAUCCAAUGAAUGCCAAGAAAAUGUACAGCAAAUGUGCCACUUGAAUAUCUAGUAUGAAGCUGGUAAUGAAGAAAUUGCCAUUUCUGAAGCAGAUAUGAAAUAUGAUCUGCUUAAUUGUUAAGGCAACUGACCUUUCAAAAGUGCAGAGUCUUAUUAAAAGAGGGGAGGGGUAGAAGCAGAAUAAUAGUCAUAUGUCUAACCUGCCCCAGUUAACUCCUCUUGUUAAAUUAUAAGCCAGUUAUCUUUUUUAGAUAGUAUUUUUGUCACUUGGAUAAUCACAGGAAAUAUAUAAGAAAAGAGCUUGGACUAACUUGAGAAGUUGGACAUGGAAAGCAAGACCAAGUUCCAGUUGGGUUUAAUUUUCCCUCUUGGUUAUUUUCGGACACAAAGGGAAUGCUUAAAACUGAGUUUAGUAAUAAAAAGCAUAAAUCUCUUCUGUAACUUUUAUAAACCACAGGGAGGUUUCAAUCCAUGCAUUUUCCUUCAUUACUCAAGAUUAUAAAUCUGUUUUUAAAAUACAUCUAAACAAACAGUUGAGAAACAAAAGUUUGGCAUGUUGUCAGAUCCCCUUAAGAGGAAGAGGUUAAGCUGUAAAGUAGUGGCCCUGUUUUGAUGCCAGAACAUUCAUAUGCUGUUUGUUCUGGAUUUCUUUUAAAUGCAUGUAUUUUAAAUACUGGUUAAAUCUUAGAAUCUUGGCUAUAUCUUAGAAUUCUGGCUCUUGGUAACCAUAUUACAGAAGUCUAUAUUGUAAAAGCCUAAAGAUCUGGACAAGUUUCCAACAACCUUGUUUCCAUGAGUAUAUAAUUUUGGCAGACACCUGAAUUCUUUGGGACACUGUGUCUGUGUAUGUGUGUGUGUGUGUGUGUGUGUGUGUGCGCUUGUAUCUUGAAGUUGUUGCACUUCAAAACCACAGCUGCUGUAAAUUCUUAAACACUGGAGAGCCAUCCUUUGGUUUAAAUGGUAGAGGGUUAGUGGAAGUGCACACGUUGUUUUUAGCCCAGGGGUAGUAACAAACUCUUACUAGCCAACUAGAAAAUUAUUUUGUUGACGAGAUGUCCCUUUUAGGAGGGUUUGUUUCCUGAAAGAAUGCCAACUUUUUUUGUUGUUCUUUCAGUAUUGGCUUGAGUGACCUGUUCUCCUGAGUGCUCUAGUGUCUCCAGUUGUGGGGGGGAAAGAUGAUGGAGGGGAACAGAAACUGGACUUGAUGUUUGCGGUUUGAGAGGCAAGAAAAUAAAAUAACUUUCUACCUCUAAAUUGAGGCUUAGGAGUAAAAAGCAUUUUGUCCUAAAUUUAUCAUUUAAAAUAGCAUCAGUAACUUUUGAGCUCAUGUCAAUCAAGCAUUGGCAGUCAGAGAUUUUAUAGGGAAGACUAAGUAAAUCCAGUUUCCAAGAACCUAAACUGAUUGAGGCUCCAAGAGUCAGACCAACAAAAGUUUUAUUCUGUGUUGUUUACUGGUAAGAAUAUUAUUAUCUUGAUACUACCUCUCAAGGGUAUUGUUACAAAAUGCCACUUAUGGUUAAAGAGAUAGAUACAAAGAGUUCUAUUUGACAGAAGCUUGAAACUCUGGCAUCUAUCUGCCCAACGAUGGGGGCUUUCGUUCUGUAAUUUAAUCCUUUGUAGAUACAUUAUUUGUGUGUAAUUUUAUACGUGUUCAUAUUUUUCUCAUUUUGCAUUGUGUAAAGUGUACAAAAUCUCAAAGUAUAAAAUACUGCUUAUAUUGCUUGUAAUUUACAGUGUGUAAAUAUUUUCUAAUUGUGUACAUUGAUGGGGGGGACAAGUGGGUUAUUCAGGUUUUUUUUUAAUGACCCUUUUGUAUUGCAGUUUCAACAGAUAACUGUCCAUCAAAUUUAAAACCACUUUGAUACAUUUUUAUUUAACAGUUCCAAUAAGAAAAAAAUCUCUAUUUUUAAUUAUAUUUCUCCUUUAGAAAAAAAAUACUUCAUGGUCCCUCUAAAAUAAAUGGCCAGACCUCAGUUUAGGCCCUUGUAUUUAUGACUCUGGUAGAGGUCUUCAGACUCCAGGUCAUAGUCCAGUCAGUAUUUGCAUUUGGGUUCUCAUGAAAACUUUGUGACUCUCUUUUAGCACAAGUAGCCCAUGGUUUUUCUUCCAAAUCAAGUAUUUUACUUCUCCCUUGAGUCCCCAUGCUUUGUCUCCCUCCUGCUGCUAUUGCCCGGUGAAUGGGAUGGUAGAGAGGGAGAAAUGUUCAUUGCACAGAGAAUGUCAGGCCACUUUGGGGACUUGGCAAACGAAGCUUGCACUGAGUGGUGGUGUGUUUGGCAAUAUUACUGUGCCAAAAAUCACCUUGUCUAAUUUUAUGGAUAUGUAUGGCAAACUUAUUACCCUUCUUGCAAGCUGCACAUUAAGGUACUUGUAAGUGUUUAUGCUUUUGUGUGUAACUGUUUGCCUUUUCUAACUGCUUUUCUUGUUACUGAAAAUAUAAUUCUACUAGUUUUAUCACAUUAAGAGGCUCUCCAUGCACAAAAUGCAUUGAUGUAGCCGUAAAGUAACAGCAUUUGUACAUUUUCUAUCUCCUGAUGGCAGUGGUGCCUUUGUCACCUUUUGGAAGGUUUGCAUUUUGUUUCUGCUUUCAAGCGCAAAUAGUAGCUUGCUUUCAGCUUCACAAAAAUCUCCUCAAAUGUAAAAGAUACAAAAUGGCGUGUUAUCAUCCAGGCUUAGUUGGAGUAUUUGCAUUUUUAUUUUUAUCAAAACAAAUAUAAUUGGUGGGGACUGGCCAGUAAUAAUGUGUGGCGUCUUUAAGCCAAGAGUAAUUUUUAAAUUAAAAAUGAAAAUUUUAAGAGGUAGCCCAUUAAACAAGCUACUGAGUUGGAGAAUUAGGGGAUGACUGUGGUGGUUUGUCGCUAAGGAGGCAACAGUAGGGUCCAGGCGGCGGGGCACGUAGAGCAGUUAGCAUGAUCCAUGGUUAUUCCUUACUCAUGAACAGUGUCGGCGCACCUCAUUAUCUGUGCAUUUGUUUUUCCUGGGCAGUCCUGUCAGCCAGUUAAUCCACCAGCUCUUAGGAAGUAAAUACAGAUUUUUUUCUUUCCUUUUUUUUUUUUUUAAAGAUUUUAUACUACAUCUUGUUAAAGUCCUAUGAAUGUGUGUGUGUGUGUGCUAUUAAAACUGCUUUUUCUCAGUUUGAA